AUUCCCCUCUCAAUCUUUGAUCAAUGUACUUGCCAGGGAGAGCCCAAGUCCUUCAAACCUCCUCCUUUUCACCUUCAUCCUUAACUUUGUGCUAGAGCGAGACCCACACAACAACAGCCGACCCUCCCCGCCCCACCCCCACCCCCAAACCAGCCCUCGAUCCCAGCCCCCGGAGAGGACUCGCAUUUCGACUUGCGGGACACUUUUGUGCGUUCCUCUCCAGAGCGCCUCUCGUGCUCGCCCCUCUUGCGCUCGCUCUUUAUUACCUUCACCUCCUUUUCUCCCCCUUCUCUCCCUUUCUCCUUCUCGUUCUCUCCCGGAGUUGUUGUUGCCCCCCUCGCUCCUUCUCCCCCCUUUUUUCCCCUUCCCCUCCCGGGGGUGUGUGGCAACUUUUCCUCUCGCUUCUCCUCCGUCUGUUUCCCCUUAUAUGUGACCAUGGCAGUGCCGGCGGCUUUGAUCCCUCCGACCCAGCUGGUCCCCCCUCAACCCCCAAUCUCCACGUCUGCUUCCUCCUCUGGCACCACCACCUCCACCUCUUCGGCGACUUCGUCUCCGGCUCCUUCCAUCGGACCCCCGGCGUCCUCUGGGCCAACUCUGUUCCGCCCGGAGCCCAUCGCUUCGGCGGCGGCGGCGGCGGCCACAGUCACCUCUACCGGCGGCGGCGGCGGCGGCGGCGGCAGCGGAGGCGGCGGCGGCAGCAGCGGCAACGGAGGCGGCGGUGGCGGCGGCGGCGGUGGCAGCAACUGCAACCCCAACCUGGCGGCCGCGAGCAACGGCAGCGGCGGCGGCGGCGGCGGCAUCAGCGCUGGCGGCGGCGUCGCUUCCAGCACCCCCAUCAACGCCAGCACCGGCAGCAGCAGCAGCAGCAGUAGCAGCAGCAGCAGCAGCAGCAGUAGUAGCAGCAGCAGCAGUAGCAGCAGCAGCUGCGGCCCCCUCCCCGGGAAACCCGUGUACUCAACCCCGUCCCCAGUGGAAAACACCCCUCAGAAUAAUGAGUGCAAAAUGGUGGAUCUGAGGGGGGCCAAAGUGGCUUCCUUCACGGUGGAGGGCUGCGAGCUGAUCUGCCUGCCCCAGGCUUUCGACCUGUUCCUGAAGCACUUGGUGGGGGGCUUGCAUACGGUCUACACCAAGCUGAAGCGGCUGGAGAUCACGCCGGUGGUGUGCAAUGUGGAACAAGUUCGCAUCCUGAGGGGACUGGGCGCCAUCCAGCCAGGAGUGAACCGCUGCAAACUCAUCUCCAGGAAGGACUUCGAGACCCUCUACAAUGACUGCACCAACGCAAGUUCUAGACCUGGAAGGCCUCCUAAGAGGACUCAAAGUGUCACCUCCCCAGAGAACUCUCACAUCAUGCCGCAUUCUGUCCCUGGUCUCAUGUCUCCUGGGAUAAUUCCACCAACAGGUCUGACAGCAGCCGCUGCAGCAGCUGCUGCUGCUACCAAUGCAGCUAUUGCUGAAGCAAUGAAGGUGAAAAAAAUCAAAUUAGAAGCCAUGAGCAACUAUCAUGCCAGUAAUAACCAACAUGGAGCAGACUCUGAAAACGGGGACAUGAAUUCAAGUGUCGGCAGCAGUGAUGGUUCCUGGGAUAAGGAAACACUGCCCUCUUCCCCAUCCCAGGGACCUCAGGCCUCUAUAACCCACCCCCGCAUGCCUGGAGCACGUAGCCUUCCACUUAGUCAUCCUCUCAACCAUCUUCAGCAGAGCCACCUUCUGCCAAAUGGACUGGAACUUCCUUUUAUGAUGAUGCCCCACCCUCUAAUUCCUGUCAGCCUACCUCCAGCAUCUGUCACCAUGGCAAUGAGCCAGAUGAACCACCUCAGCACCAUUGCAAAUAUGGCAGCAGCAGCACAAGUUCAGAGUCCCCCAUCCAGAGUUGAGACAUCAGUUAUUAAGGAGCGUGUUCCUGAUAGCCCCUCACCUGCCCCCUCUCUGGAGGAGGGGAGAAGGCCUGGCAGUCACCCAUCAUCACAUCGCAGCAGCAGCGUGUCCAGCUCCCCUGCUCGGACUGAGAGCUCUUCUGACAGAAUCCCGGUCCAUCAGAAUGGGUUGUCCAUGAACCAGAUGCUGAUGGGCUUAUCACCAAAUGUACUUCCUGGGCCCAAAGAGGGAGAUUUGGCCGGUCAUGACAUGGGACAUGAGUCAAAAAGGAUGCAUAUUGAAAAAGUUCAUAUCAUCCUUACUAGGAUUCAACUUGAUUUUACGAAAAACACUGGAUUAAAUAUGCAUAAAAGACUCCAAUGUGGGAUGUGUGCUGAUUCCAGUGUAUCCUCCAGACAUUACUGAGACCAAAAGUGAUGCAAUUACAUUUUCCUUUUGUUGCUUUUGCAUUUCUUGUAGUGAACCUAAGUCCUUCAGAUCCCAAUAAACAUACAACCUAAAUUCUUCACAUACCAUAAACACAGACCUUGUUGUUUCCUGACUUAAAUCCAGUUUUCAAACUUAGGCAGUGGGUGAAAGGAGAGAGAAGUCUAUGCCAAUAAUAUUGGAAAAUCUCUUUUAUGCCAUUAAUUUCAGUUCCUCAAGGAUCUUCAAUCUUUCCUUUCAUGAAUGUAUUUUAUUUUGCUGUGAUCUUUGUUAGACUAAGAGCUUUCAUAGACUUGGAAUAAUUUCUGAUAGUAAAAUAGCUGAGCUUUUAAUCUCCUGAAAAUGCUCACUUAUUGUUUAAAUUGAAUAUUACUUUUGGCAUCAAAUAGCCAAAGUUCUCAGCUUCCUUAUAUAGAGGUAGACUGGCUUAUAAGUUCUUAUUUUCUCUAUAACAUGUGGAUGGUACAGUGAGAAACUUUGAAGUUAGACUUUAGAUUAGAGUUUAUAUAUUUUCUUUGCAGGAAAAUUUGGCUUCCAAUAAAAUUCAUAUAUGAAACACUCAUGUAUUUUCAGUGUUCUGGAAAUCAUGGCAGUGGUUUAAGAUUAAACAGACUUUUCUCAUUGUUUUAGACAAGCCAAAGAGGAGAGAGAUUUAUUUAUUGUGGAAAAAUUUUAAAAUAGAAAUUUAGAAUAAUGAUAAUGACAUUAUUGAUAUUUAAAAGUCAGCUAUCGACACAUGUAUUUUUCUCUAUCAAUUCUUUAUAGCUAAUAAUUUAAAGUUUUUACCAUGAAAUGAAGAAACAGCCUGUAUGAUAAUAACUCAGAUGAUUAAGGAAUAAGUUAUAUUUUCAUAUUGUGAUGUAAUAAGUUUAUCUGAACCACAAUGUACUUUUUAUACCUGAUGUACAACUUUGAACUUUGUUUUUUAUUUUAUUUUUCAAGUAUGUAUGUAUGUAUCUAUGUAUGUAUUUAUUUAUUUAUUUGAGACGGAGUUUCGCUCGUUUCCCAGGCUGGAGUGCAAUGGCGCAAUCUCAGCUCACUGCAACCUCCACCUCCUGGGUUCAAGAGAUUCUCCUCCCUCAGCCUACUAAGUAGCUGGGAUUACAGGUGCCCACUGCCAUGCCCAGCUAAUUUUUUAGUAUUUUUAAUAGUGAAGGAGUUUCACCAUGUUGGUCAGGCUGGUCUCGAACUCCUGACCUCAGGUGAUCUGCCUGUCUUGGCUUCUCAAAGUGCUGGGAUUACAGGAGUGAGCCAUCGUACCCGGCCUGAAAUUUGUGAAGAUGAAAAAAAAAAAAAAAAAAAAAAACUGGGCAAAUAUCAGUGACUUUUCCACAAAUGUCAAUAAUUUUUUAAAAAGGACAGCAAGCUAAAGGAUGUUAAAUGUUUAAAAAGCUCCAUAGAAUUCUACUGCAACUCAUUUUUAGAACCCUUAAAAUUAAUAUAAUUGAAAUAAAUUGCAAAGCAAAUUUCACAGGGUAUUCUUUUUCUUUAAUAACAAGAAUUUAACCCUUAACACCAUGUAAAAAUGUCAGUGUUUUCAUUUGAUUAUGGCAGACUUCUCUUUUCUGACAACAAAUGAUUCAUGUGAUAUUAUCAAUAAAAAUGUAAAAUGCCAUAUAAAUGAACUUAUAUAUGGAAAAUGUAACCUAUAGAAUAAGAUAUGUAUACAAAUCGCAAGUCCAGUGUGCUUCUUGUAAAGAAAAAGUUUUAUUCAGAUCUUAGAGUCAAGCAAUGAAUUUAUUUCUUUAAUUGAUGUUUUUAUAAUUGAUACUUUUAUUGAAGGUGUUUCAUAGUUUAUUUGCAUAAUUAAAUAUUAAGGCAAACUAUGCCAGUUUGUUUUAUAAUCAUGAUCAUUAUGUGAAAUAAGCUCAAACAUACAAUAAAGUUUAAAAGCCCUUACAAAAGACAUUUCAGGAAACUAUAAAAAUACUUCUUUGAGUAACUGAUACUCAUUGUCAAGGAAGCAAUAUUUCUUUGGUGUUGGUUAGUAAAUCUCUUGCACCUAGUUGUAAAGUAUUCUGAAGUAAAAUUUCUAUAGAACCAUAAAGAAUCAGGUUUUUUAAAAAAUAAAAUUACAUAUGAACUUCAUUAUCCAUAAGGAAUAGCAUCAUAAUUUGCACUUAUUACUUAUGAAAAUAUUUCUAGGAUGGUAACGUAAUUCAUUAUUACAUAAUAUUUAUUUCUCUCCUACUUGAGAAAAAGUGCUAUGUAACAUGAUAAUCUAAAUUUAACAAUACAUAAAAUAAAAAACAUAGCAUUUCCUUUAUAAUAGGCAUAUUAAUAGGACAAGUAUAUGUGUUAAGGAAAGGGUUUAUGGGUUAAUAGAUAAACAAUCAUAUAUUUUUAUGUUGGUGAUCAUUUAAUCAGUGACUUUAAAAUUUCUUUCCAUUUUAAUUUAGGCAAUAUUAUAGAAGUUGAAGUUGAGUUUGUUCAAUGUGAUAUUUUUGUCAUAGACUAAAUACCCUAAGUCAUGAGAGUUACAUAAAUUAAGAUAAAACAAAAACCUACAGGUUGCUGUAAUGUUCAGAGCUCUAUAAGGUUUCAAAAUGAUCUUUACUCCAUUGUAAGAAUUAUGAUGUCAUAUGGAAUGAAAGCUCCAUAAAAAAUCUGGAUUUUUUGAUAUGUAGUAUCAGUUUCAUUUAUUAAUGAUAGUUAUGGUGAUAUAUGAUUCUGUGAUAACCCACAUAUAAUAUCCAUCCUAAGAAUGACAUGACCAAAGGCAUUUGUAAUUAUAUUUACUUCUGAAAGAUUAUGGUUUAUAGUUAAAACAAAAGAGGCAUCCUGUCAUUUUCUAAACCCGUUAAAUGUGACAGAAUCUAUUUUUCUGCCAACUUGUGAGGACCAGGCAGAGAGCAAAUUUGCUGUGGUCAGCUAAGUGUAACCACUGAGCAGGAAAGUGAAUUUAAUAAUGCAUUAUUGUUCUUCACUGAAGGUGAACUGUUACAGUGCCUUUGUUAUAGCAGACUUUGCCUCUGCUUAGGUUUCCAGAUGCUGUGUAGAUUACCUGAUUAAAAUCUCUAAUGCAUGAUAAAAUGUACCAGGUAUACUUUUAUAUUAACAGAAAUGCAUCCAUUUUAGGGCCAUAAUACUGAAUCUAAUUGGAAACAUUUUCCAAUUAUAUUAUCUAGUGAAUUUAUAUUAUAAAUAAAUAUGAUAUACAAUAUAGAAUAAAUGACAUGGAAGCCUAAAUUCAUAAAGUUUAUCUCAUGCCAAUGAUAGAUCAUUUUAUUGAUACUGAAAUAAAAUUUACCAUAUUUUUGAUGCAAUUAAGAAUAUGAUCUUUUAAAUCAUCUUUAUUUUGAAUGUUAUUUUAAAACAAAGUAAAAAAUACAAGAUACUCUUUAAAAUACAACCAGUUCUUUCAUGACCGCAUUCUUUGUAUUGCCCUUCCUUUUCCAGUUCCAUCUUUUUUGAUAUUUUCUCUUACAAAUACAUUGAUCAACCAUAGUACUUUCAUAAAAGUUUUAGUGCUGAUUGAGUUGAAAUGACAGGAAAUAAAUAAAGCUUGGUGUAAUUUACUUUCUCUAUUUUACCCAAAUUUAAUUCACUAAAAAAUAAAAUAUGUGUAAAAUAGCAUCUUAAGAGAAUUAGCCAGAAAUACAAACUUUAUUUAGGAAAGCAGAAAUCCUCGGGGAAUUUGUGCACAUUGAUUCCUUUUUUACUGCAAGUUUUUAUAUUGAUUAUAGUUCCUAUCAGUAACAUUUUCAGAGAGUUUAUGGAUAUAUUGCAGAUUGUGGGCUUCUGUUAACCACUGGUAUUAUAGGCUCAUGGUUGAUAAUCAAACAGUUAAUUUUAUAGUUAAUUCUGACAGGUUUCUAGAAAGUCUUUCGAAGGAAAGAUUUUCUGUAGUCCACAACUGAAAGGGUGCACACAACCUAAUCUUUGGUUGUCAUUGCUGAACUUUAUGGUUAAGAGGCAAAGAAAAGCAUUUUUCUGAAUAUCAAGAGCACCCAUCAAUGAAUAUCACUACGGGCCAUAGAACAUGCAAGUUCAAGAGACAGAAGCAAAACAGGAGUUGACAAAAAAUAGUAACAGCUAGACCCGGUGUGAGAGUGUUUUUAUACAACAGUGAAUGAGAAAAUGAUUUUCACUAUUUCUUGCCUCUUAACAAAUAGAGCUGUGUGUAUAUGGCAGAACCAUAACAAUUUCAGCUGUUAUACAUUUGCAUUUUGAAUAUUUAGACAUUAAACAUUUAAAUCUCAUUCAAAAGAUUAAAAAAAUAAAAUAUAAGGAACUGUGCAACAUCGAGGAAUGAAAGAUGACUUUUAUGUGAUAAACAUAAAUAUCCAAUAACUGCCUAAAAUAAACUCUGAAAUUACCAUGUUGACAAUGUUAUUUCCUCUUUUUAAAAGGACAAGAAAUAUGAAACGAAAUUGAAAUGCAACAAAUACAUGUUUUAACCUGACCCUGAAUCUUGUGUUUAUUUUUGUUUUAAAUAAAAUCUAGAGCUCCGUAGGUAAGAUAGGUGCCAGCAUUUGAAACUGCAGUCAUUUUUAAACUGAGUAUGUUUUUAUUUUUAAACUAAAUGUACUAUGCUGUUUGCAUUUCCUAAAAAUAUCCAGAAACUCUGGUAGUUUGUUGUUCAGUGCUCCCCUGGAGAAUUCAUGUGAAGGUCUAAAUAUUUUAUACUGUUGAUUUUAUUAAAAUGUGAAGAUCCAUUUUGUGACCGUGUAAAUGGAAUGUCAGUGUUUCCCUUCGAAGUUCACAUUCCCUUGCCUGUGUUCUGCAUAUUCCUUUUCCUUGCUCAGAAUUCUUAUAUAGGUAAGGAAGACCUUCCAAGGUUUCUUUUGCCACGCUUGCUUCUCCAAACACUACAAUAAAAUCAUUUUGAUGAAGUAA